UAAGGAACUGUGGGUAGAUGGUUUGCAGGACCACAUACACACACAAAAUAGCCGACUAAAGAAAGCGGUGGAGAUCGAGAUCAGUAAGUUUGAUUUGGGAACAAAACCCUGGAGACUCUAUAGGUAGGUGACUGUUGGGGGUGGACAGGCGCUGAAGACUUGGAUUGGUUUAGACCUAGAAGGAAGUGGCAUUUGAUUGGUUAUUAUAAGUGAAAAGGGCCCCUCCCCGGGUGAGAUAUGCCAGCCCCAUAAUUAGGACCUGAAAAUCUCUGCCAGGCCUGCCUUUGUGACGUGGCCCAGUCUACCUCAGCUAUGGAACAGGCCUUGACUGGUGAGGCCCAAAGCCGGUGGCCCCGCAGAGGCGGGAGUGGGGCCAUGGCUGAGGCGCCUGGGCCCAGUGGCGAAUCCCGAGGACACUCAGCCACUCAGCUGCCAGCGGAAAAAACUGUCGGGGGACCAUCGAGGGGCUGCUCAAGCUCCGUGCUCAGAGUGUCCCAGUUGGUGCUCCAGGCCAUCUCCACUCACAAAGGGCUGACUCUGGCAGCUCUCAAGAAGGAGCUCCGAAACGCCGGCUACGAAGUGCGCAGGAAGAGCGGCCGCCACGAAGCGCCCAGGGGGCAGGCCAAGGCCACGCUCCUCCGGGUCAGCGGCAGCGACGCCGCCGGCUACUUCAGGGUCUGGAAGGUUCCCAAGCCCAGGAGAAAGCCGGGACGCGCGAGGCAAGAGGAGGGCACGCGCGCUCCCUGGAGGACCCCAGCCGCGCCCCGGAGCUCCCGGAGGCGCCGCCAGCCCCUUCGCAAGGCGGCCAGGAAGGCCAGAGAAGUGUGGAGACGGAACGCGAGGGCGAAAGCCAAGGCCAAUGCCAGGGCGAGGAGGACCAGGAGGGCAAGGCCGAGAGCCAAGGAGCCGCCGUGUGCCAGAGCCAAGGAGGAAGCGGGAGCGACAGCGGCAGACGAGGGGCGAGGACAGGCCGUGAAGGAAGACACCACGCCGAGGUCAGGGAAGGACAAGAGGCGAAGCUCCAAGCCCAGGGAAGAGAAGCAGGAGCCCAAGAAGCCCGCACAGCGGACCAUCCAGUAGCCAACGCGGGCUAAAACCGACCGGACAUCUAGCGGGCAGGGGAAGACUCCACUAAAGACUUCCACAAAGACCUCCCCUAAAUCUGAAGGUCUUCCUGAUCCAGUUGGGAAUGCAUCUUGUGGGAGCAGCUUCACUCCCACCACGGACCAAUGCCUUUCCCCCAUAGGCCCCAAGAAGAGCGGCUGUCACACUCAUUGAAAUGAAAUGGACCUCUAGACCA